ACCCCGCGCCAGCAGCUCGGUGGCCGAGUCGGUCCCGCGGCCGGCGGAUCGGGCGCGCGCGUCGGGGGUCGUCCGGCUGCCAGGCAGGGCGAGCACGCGCCGGGAGGCCUUGGAGGCGUAGGGGGCGGGGGUACGGCUCGCCUGCUCGCAAGAUGGCGGACGAGGACGGGGAAGGGAUUCAUCCCUCAGCCCCUCACAGGAACGGAGGUGGCGGCGGCGGCGGGGGGUCUGGGCUCCACUGCGCCGGGAACGGCGGCGGGGGAGGCGGCGGCCCGCGGGUCGUGCGCAUCGUCAAGUCCGAGUCCGGCUACGGCUUCAACGUGCGGGGCCAAGUGAGCGAGGGCGGGCAACUGCGGAGCAUCAACGGGGAGCUGUACGCGCCGCUGCAGCAUGUGAGCGCCGUGCUGCCCGGGGGGGCGGCCGAUCGGGCCGGGGUGCGCAAGGGGGACCGCAUCCUGGAGGUGAACCACGUGAAUGUUGAGGGGGCGACACACAAGCAGGUGGUGGACCUGAUUCGAGCAGGCGAGAAGGAAUUGAUCUUGACAGUGUUAUCUGUACCUCCUCAUGAGGCAGAUAACCUAGAUCCCAGUGACGACUCGUUGGGACAAUCAUUUUAUGAUUACACAGAAAAGCAAGCAGUGCCCAUAUCGGUCCCCAGAUACAAACAUGUGGAGCAGAAUGGUGAGAAGUUUGUGGUAUAUAAUGUUUACAUGGCAGGGAGGCAGCUGUGUUCUAAGCGGUACCGGGAGUUUGCUAUCCUACACCAGAACCUGAAGAGAGAGUUUGCCAACUUUACAUUUCCUCGACUCCCAGGGAAGUGGCCAUUUUCAUUAUCAGAACAACAAUUAGAUGCCCGACGUCGGGGAUUGGAAGAAUAUCUAGAAAAAGUGUGUUCAAUACGAGUAAUUGGUGAGAGUGACAUCAUGCAGGAAUUCCUAUCAGAAUCCGAUGAGAACUACAAUGGUGUGUCCGACGUAGAGCUGAGAGUAGCAUUACCAGAUGGAACAACGGUUACAGUCAGGGUUAAAAAGAACAGUACUACAGACCAAGUAUAUCAGGCUAUCGCAGCAAAGGUUGGCAUGGACAGUACGACAGUGAAUUACUUUGCCUUAUUUGAAGUGAUCAGUCACUCCUUUGUACGUAAAUUGGCACCUAAUGAGUUUCCUCACAAACUCUACAUUCAGAAUUAUACAUCAGCUGUGCCAGGCACCUGCUUGACCAUUCGAAAGUGGCUUUUUACAACAGAAGAAGAAAUUCUCUUAAAUGACAAUGACCUUGCUGUUACCUACUUCUUUCAUCAGGCAGUCGAUGAUGUGAAGAAAGGUUACAUCAAAGCAGAAGAAAAGUCCUAUCAAUUACAGAAGCUAUACGAACAAAGAAAAAUGGUCAUGUACCUCAACAUGCUAAGGACUUGUGAGGGCUACAAUGAAAUCAUCUUUCCCCACUGUGCCUGUGACUCCAGGAGGAAGGGGCACGUUAUCACAGCCAUCAGCAUCACGCACUUUAAACUGCAUGCCUGCACUGAAGAAGGACAGCUGGAGAACCAGGUAAUUGCAUUUGAAUGGGAUGAGAUGCAGCGAUGGGACACAGAUGAAGAAGGGAUGGCCUUCUGUUUCGAAUAUGCACGAGGAGAGAAGAAGCCCCGAUGGGUUAAAAUCUUCACGCCAUAUUUCAAUUACAUGCAUGAGUGCUUCGAGAGGGUGUUCUGCGAGCUCAAGUGGAGAAAAGAGGAAUAUUAGUUAGAGACUGAUUAUCUCAUGUGAGCCAGGACAUUCUUCCAGCAAGGUUGGCCUCUGGAUGGUGAACGGGCUGUGCAAAAAAGCCCUGCUUCUUCCCUUGUCUAGAGGGUGGACAUUGGCUACAGGCUCUUCCAUCUCUCAUGACUUCAUGGACCCUCCUCUGCCAGUUUUUUAAAUCAGAUCACCCUCCAUGUUGUUCCUGACCCACAGGGGAAGCUGUCCUCAGUUGUAGCCGUCUUGACUGGAUGAGUCCUGGCAGUCUUUCUAGGCGAACCAAGAAUGUUUGUGUGAGGGAAGGUGUUUGCUGUUGCUUUACUGCUGUCUGUAUGUGCCAGUGCUGGAACAGAAUUUGGAAGAUUCUGAAUAAUUAGUUACUUAUUCUCAAAGAAAAUCUUUGAAAGAAUCAGGAGGUCAAGUCAAGAACAUGAAAAUUUAUAUUUUAGUACAGUAGAAAGAACAUUGGGCUCUGGGAAUUUUAUCUGGGUUUUCUCCUGGCUUUUUUUUCCCUCUGUGUAAUUUUGGGUAAAUCAGCCUCCCUAGCUUUCAGUUUUCUCUUCUGUGAAACAGGAAGACUGAACCACGUAAUUAAUAUCCAAGGUCCCUUCCGGCUCUAAAAGGCUAUGAUUCUAGAUGAGAAGUUAUAUCAAGAAAGAUGUGGCCAAUCAGAUUGAGUCAUCCAGGCAUACCUUUUUAGCUUCUGUUUGUGGAGUUGUCUCCAGAUAAGAGGAGAUGUGCCUUCCCAAUAACUCUUUUUUUUUUUCCUUUCAGAACAUUUUCCAGAUGGCGAGGUCACAGCAGAGAGAUGUGGCCACCUAGCCUUUCCUUAUCCCCUUCCCUUCCCUUCACCCCCAUCCUCUUACUCCUUUCAUGUCCCAUUUCAGACAGAGUAACCAUUAACAAAAAAGAAGAGAAAAAGUUAAAGUCGUUAUAUUCAAAAGCCCUAAACUAAAUAUUAUUAAUAACCCCCUCUGAAUUUCAUGUCUCUGGAAUUGAGGUGGUAGUGAACAGCAGAUCGGUCAGCACCAGAAGUCAACUGAGUUAAGGCAGGAAAAGAAAUAAGCCCAACCAACUUGCCAAAGGUAUCUUUGUCCUUUCACCUGGGCCUCAUACCAACAGCCUCUCCUUGUACUAUAUUUUUAAAACUGGAACUAUGAACUUCAUCCAUUUGCACUGUUCAGACAUAUAUAUGUAUGUAUGUAAAAAUUAUAUAUACACAAAUUAGCUGCACGUAUAUACAUAUAUAUAUUUCUUUUUAAAUUUCAUAUUGAUGGCAGUACCUUUUUUAGCUUGUGUUUUUACACACCUUUCACUAGAAUCCAUGACCUCCCUCGUGCUCUCUUUCUUUUGAAACAAACUUUAAAAAGGAAAAAAAAGCAUUUUACAGGGAAAAAUACCUCUCCUCAUGAAGGACUUGAAAAGUUUACAACCUGCUUGGAUUUUUGCCCCUUUUUUUGUAUUGAGUAUAGAUUCCGGCUCAUGGGUUGCCAUAGAGUCUAGGAACAAGGAGUAUAGUUUCUUUAUCUUCCAAGAGGGUGCUGGGGAGGAGAAAGAGGUGUGUUUCUCAAGGUUAACAGGCUGUAGUUCUGCAGGGAGAGCCUGAAGUCCUGGUAUGGGCUCUUGAUUCUGUGACAAUUUUUUUGAUCCAUCUAUUUCUCUCACUCCUGGCUUUCUAGCCACAUUCUGCACCUCCUUCCUGCUUUCCUAGAGCCUCGGUAUGCUUUCCCUCAACCGACCCUGGCUCAGGAGGUUGAUGCCAUGGGAACCUGAACCUGAAACACUUCAUGGUAGUAAUUUCCUGUUUUCCUUGCCUUUUUUUUUUUUUUUUUUUUUUUUUUCUGAGACAGGGUCUUACUCUGUCGCCCAGACUGGAAUGUGGUGGCAUGAACAUAGCUCACUGUUACCUUGAAUUCUGGGCUCAGGUGAUCCUUCCGCCUCACCCUCCUGAGUAGCUGGGACUACAGGUGUGCACCACCACACCUGGCUAAUUCUUCUUAAAAUUUUUUUGUAGAGACAGGGUCUCACUAUGUUGCCCAGGCUGGUCUCAAACUCCUGGCCUCAGGUGAUCCUCUUGUCUCAGCCUCCCAAAGUGCUGGGAUUACAGGCAUGAGCCACUGUGUCCUUCCCUGCCUUUUUUGCAGCAGGGAUAGUACUCAGGACCAGAGUUAAGCUGAUACCUUAGGCACACAGGUUGGACUUACAUAGAGGAAAGAAAGCAAGAAAUGCCCUAUGUACAUGAGGUUUUACCUCCUCCAUUCCUGACCAAUAACCACCCAUAACUACGGCAUUCUCUGUGACUUCCUUAAACAGCAGUGAUGGGAAGGGAUCCAAUAGUAUCUUCAAGGCCUUGGGGAAACUUGCAGUGGGUCAGUGGUCUGUGCCAACCAAACGAUAGCCCCAUCCAAGCCAGCUGAGAACCUAGGAAGGAGUAGUAGGAAUAUGGUUGAUUAGAUUGGAUCUCCCAAGUUUUAAUUGAAAGGAGACUGAACGAAAACCUUUCUGCUUUCUGUCCGUUAAAGAGCUCCUCAUCUGAUCUUGCAGCUAGACCCUUUGAGACUUAAGAGCUGCAUCCCAGGAUCAGAAGCCAGGGCUAAUUGGGGUAGGACAAUAUUCCCAGCCCCUAAGCUCUGUAGAUAAUGCAUAAGAAGCACCAAGUCAGGCUCAGAUGCAACUAAAACACAUCUUUGAGCCUUUUCUUUUUCCCUUCUCCCCUUUCUAAACAAAAACCUUCCUAGGAUGGCAUCUUUUGCUCUAACUGGGAGACAGUCAUAAUUGGUUGUAGUCAAUUCUACUAAGCAGUGUUGGGGUGGUUGGAAAGUCUCUUUUUUGUAAUUUGUUUUUGCAAAUCAUUGUGAGGCCACUUUUUCUUUCUUUCUUUCUUUCUUUCUUUCUUUCUUUCUUUCUUUCGUUCUUUCGUUCUUUCGUUCUUUCUUUCUUUCUUUCUUUCUCUUUCUUUCUUUUGCUUUCCUUCUUUCAUCUCUUUUUUGUAAUUUGUUGUUGCAAAUCAUUGUGAGGCCACUUUUCUUUCCCCUUCCUUCCUUCCUUUUUUUCUGUUUUUUUUUUUUUUUUUUCCCAGAGUCUUGCUCUGUCGCCCAGGUUGGAGUGCAGUGGCACGAUCUCGGCUCACUGCACCCUCUGCCUCUUGGGUUCAAGCGAUUCUCCUGCCUCAGCCUCCCAAGUAGCUGGGAUUACAGGCAUACACCACCACGCCCCACUAAUUUUUUGUAUUUUUGGUAGGGCGGGGUUUCACCAUGAUGGCCAGGUUGGUUUUGAACUCCUGACCUCAAGUAAUCUGCCCACCUCGGCCUCCCAAAGUGCUAGGAUUACAGGAGUGAGCCACUGCGCCUGGCCCACUUUUCUUUCUUUCCUUCUUAUUUUGUUAUGCUGGCAGCCAUUUGCCCCUGCAUGGUAUGGGAUCAAAGAGGACAGCCUUUCCUCCCUCACCUUCUCCAAAUCUAGGUGAAAUCACAGAGUACAAAACGUGAGAAUGCUGAAUGUGUAAAGUUGCAGAGGGAUCCCUAAUUUGAAGACUUUGACACAGAACUAACUUCUUUUGACUUAAAUGAAUUUAAAAUGAGCCAAAGGACCCUGAAAAGAAGACAUGUUGAUUUCCCACUCCUAGAUGCUAAAGAGACUUGGCACCAGCUUUGUUCAAACUGUAAAAAUAGCAAUUUGCCCCUACUCGCUCAGAGUGGGACAGUAGUGAACAGAGCUGGGAUUCCAUGCGACAGCUUGAAUGCUGACCUUCAGACAUGAGACAUAGGGAUUUGGAGGCCCCUUAGAAUGGGUAGAUGGUGUUAUGUUCCCUUUCUGGCAUAGCAUUCACUUGGUGCUUUGGAGAUUAGGUGAGGGCCCUAUAGGUAGUUGGCCUGUUGGCAGAAUUUAUUUAGGAACAGCCCUUUUGAAAGUGUCCCAGUAACAACGCACCCAGCUGCAGCAAGGAGGUGGGGAAGGAGGGCACCCCAAAGGACAGCGCCUUCUUCUCUUCCACCCAUGCACGGCCUUGGGUGAUGGAGGCGGGUUCCCUGUGGCUGCGUGGAUCCCAUAGGAUCAAGCCCUUCUUUGCAUGAAGCAGUGUUGUGACUCUUCUCUCUCCCCUUCCUCUGCACUUCCUUUCUGUAAUCCCUACUGUUCUUCUUAGUCCCAGCUUCUGCCCAGGGAGGCUUCUACCCAGACUUCUUUUGCAAUUUGUCCCUGGGAAGAGGGGGUCUCCCAGUGCCCCCAGCUUCAUCCCAGCAGAACCAGCAGGAUCCUCCUGGUCUCUCACUGGCCUUCCUCCACACUUGGUUUCUAUCCUCAGGGGUAGAAGCUCAGAGCUUUUUAUGGCCCAGGAGAAAAUGUAGACCCUGAGAAACCUGUCCCUGCAGAAAGGUUCCCUUGGGCCAUGCUUUGGGCCCUCUGCUCUUUAUAUGUUUAUUCUAUUCUCCAUUUUUCCACCCCGUCCUUACCCUAGGCCUAAACACAGGUACAGAUAUGUGCAUGCUCAGGGCAGCUCCUAGGCCUGGACUGAGCUCUCAGGGGGGAAUUAGAUAAAUAUUCCAACAUCCUCAUGCCUGGCCCAUUUAGUUUCAUCCUUUAGUUACCCAGGCCAGUAGCUUUGGGUUAUCCCUUCCUGUAGCUCCAAACCCAGCACUUGGAGCAGCAAAAUAGGGCACUGACAGGAGAUGAAACUCUCUCCUAUCUCAGAAUUUGCCAACUUCUGGGCUGGGCUCCUAGGAGGUAGUUUUCUUGAAGGGGACUGCAUCCUAGUUGACCUGAAUUUUCCAGACCAGGAGGGACUGCUGUGCUCUCCCUUCUCGCCAUCAUACUGUUUGGCUAGAUUCAUUCAGCAGUAGAAGCUGUUUGAUCUGUUGACCCCAGCAUACUGCUGUUUCUUCACCAGCUUCAUUGUGUCACAGUAGCUUCCUUUGGGAGGAUGAUGUGAUAGAACACUCAGAGAGAGGGAGGGAGAAGAGAGAUAGUGGGUAUGCUUCUCUAGCUCCCCAUCUUCCAGGUCCACCUCUUGACUUCCUGUUCCCCUAAACCUGAGCACAUCACGCCAGGCCUCUUUGCUGCCAGGACAGCAUCAGCUCACUCCUCAGCAAUAAUCUAGGGUAUGUGGGAAGGUCAGGGCUGUGGUAAGGAAUAGAAUCAAAGAGGGGAGUGAUACGGGGUGGGGGCACUUGGCCGCCUGCUAAACUUGGACAUUAAUUUUAUAUCAUGACCCCCUUUUAAGCCAGUGAGCUGGGCUUCAGUUUUUCCCAGGCCAUGCACAUUUAAUUUAUUUCAGAGAAACUCUAAUUGUAUUUUCACUGCAGUAUCUUGUAUUUUUUAUUUGUGAUUUAAGAAAUGUGAAGAGAAAAUACACAGACACAAUAAUGGCUAACAUUGUUUCUUUCAUUCCUUGUUCUAGAGCUAACCACUCUAAAAUUGUUUGGUAAUGUCACUUAGUGUAAUUAAUUGUAACAUAUUCUUUUAAAUAAAUUGAUUUAUUGAUCAAACA